AGAGUCGCGGCCGCCAGCUAGGGGCGCGGGAAGGCGGGGCUCGGAUGCAAUCGGGACCUCCUCCUGGACUGGGCCGGGGGCGGACUCCGGGACCCAGGGCGCCGGGAGCCGGCGGGCUACCUGCGAGUCGAGUUAGCGUUGUCGCCGAACCGAAGUGAGAGGGCACGGGGAAGGGUCAAAGAGCGUGCCGAAGCGCUGGAGGGAGCUUCACGGACGCGAGCUAGGCACCGGCUCGCCUAAUCCGGUGGAUGUGUGGGGAGCACAGGCCGGUCUGGUGGUGGCUGGUUACUACCAUGCCAAUGCAGCUGUGAACGAUCAGAGGUGAGUGGCGUAGCCAGAGGAAGAAGGAAAGGAUUAUGGCGGGUUGGGGAUUGGAGGAAUAGAGGGCGAGGAUGCGUGGGGCGGUGGGCGGGGCGGGGGCGCACAAGAUGAACCAAGGUCGUUCCUUUUAUCUUUCCUUCAUCAAACGCUUAGGAGCAGGGGCUUUACACCAGGCACUAUGCUGGGUACUGGAGUGAGGGAAUAUAAAGAUGAAUAGGACAGAGCCCUGCCCUGGAGUGCCGUUGGGGCGGGGAGGACAACUGUGUAUCAACAGACUGAUUUUUUUUUUUUUUUUGAGACGGAGUCUCCCUCUGUCUCCCAGGCUGGAGUGCAGUGGCGCAAUCUCGGCUCACUGGAACUUCCACCUCCUAGAUUCAAGCGAUUCUCCUGCCUCAGCCUCCCGAGUAGCUGGGAUCACAGAUGAGCGCCACCAUGCCCGGCUAAUUUUUUUUAUUUUUUUAAUUUAUUAUUAUUUUUUAUUUUUAGUAGAGAUGGGGUUUCGCCAUGUUGGCCAGGCUGGUCUAGAACUUGACCUCAGGUGAUCCACGCGCCUCGGACUCCCAAAGUGCUGGGAUUACAGGCGUGAGCCACCACUCUCGGCCAACAGACUGAUCUUGCUUUAACUGAGGUGUCCCCCAGGGGCUGAAAGAACAGAGAAAUCCCAACCAGCAACUUCAAAAAUAAGGCAGUUUCCUUAUAUAUAUACAUAUAGGAAAAGACAUAUAUAUAUAUAUAUAUAUAUUAAUCAUAUACAUGGAGCAAUUAGAGGUACUGUUUUGUAAUUUGCGUUUCUCCCUCACUUAAUAAAUACUUGACAUCAUCCCAUUUCCACACCAAGAUCUACCGUAACAGCUAUAUAGUCUGAAUAUGAAUGUACUCUAAUUUAUUUAAUACUUUAAACAUUGAGGUUGUUUCCAGUGUUUUAUUACAGACACUGUCCUAUGAUUACCAUAAAUUCUUUAUAAGUAGAAUUUCUGGGUCAGCAUAUGUAUAGUAUGUAUACAGUUUCAAUUUGGAUGGUUAUGCCAAAUUACCUUCCAAAAAGACCACCUUUGGUUUCCACUCUCACCAGCAAUAUCUGAGCACCUGUCUCCCACAGCACUCAAGCAUCAAGCAGUCGUGCAUCAAGCAUCCAGCAGGCCCGAUCCCCGCAGGCCACCUACAGGGAAAGGCCACAGCUGCGCCCACACCUAUGAGACCUGGGAGGCCCAGCUCAAAUGGAUGGGUUUUGCCCACAGUUGGCUCCUCACUCCUCUGAUCUUCCCUCUACACAGCCCUGGGCCCCUGGCCUUGAAAAUUGCUGGGCGAAUUGCAGAAUUCUUCCCUGAUGCAGUACUUAUUAUGUUGGAUAAUCAGAAACUGGUGCCUCAGCCUCGUGUGCCCCCGGUCAUCGUCCUGGAGAACCAAGGUCUCCGCUGGGUCCCUAAGGAUAAGAACUUAGUGAUGUGGAGGGACUGGGAAGAGUCACGGCAGAUGGUGGGAGCUCUACUGGAAGAUCGGGCCCACCAGCACCUUGUGGACUUUGACUGCCACCUUGAUGACAUCCGGCAGGACUGGACCAACCAGCGGCUCAACACUCAAAUCACCCAGUGGGUUGGUCCCACUAAUGGAAAUGGAAAUGCCUGAGCCAGGGCCAGCGGGGCCCGGUUCCAAUAAAGAGACUUGGGCUGA